GCUCAGUCUUGGGGUGGGCUCCGCGGUGCAGGCCGAGCUGCGCGGAGGGCUCGGCGAUCAGCGGCGGCGGCGGCAGUGGGGAGGCCGCAGCGCCAUGGGGGGGCGUUAGACAGGCUGCGGCGGCCGAGGCGAGGGGCGGCAGCGGUUAUCUGGUCCGCGGCGACCUUCGGCCGGGCCCGGGGGUGGGAAGGCCUGGGGCGGGGGUCGUCCCUGGUUGCACGGGGCCGCGGGGCGGGGCUCGCCGGCCGUCGGGGUGCAGGAGGCCUGGGCCGCUGAAAGGAGAAGGCGCCGUCGGUCGCCAGGCCCUGCCGCCGGGCCGCUUGACGACGACGCUCCCGCGGGGGCCCCGCCUGAGGAGGACGCGGCGGCGGUGGCGGCGAGGCCGCGGGAGGCCGCGGAGGAUGGAGGAGCGGAAGGAGGAGGGCGAGGCCGAGAUCCAGGAGCACGGGCCCGAGCACUGGUUCUCCAAGUGGGAGCGGCAGUGCCUGGCCGAGGCCGAACAGGACGAGCAGCUGCCCCCCGAGCUGCAGGAGGAGGCGGCGGCCGCCGCGCAGCCCGAGCACAAGCAGCAGAAGCUGUGGCACCUCUUCCAGAACUCGGCCACCGCCGUGGCCCAGCUCUACAAAGACCGAGUGUGUCAGCAGCCAGGACUUUCUCUCUGGGUCCCCUUCCAAAACGCAGCCACCGCCGUCACCAAUCUCUACAAAGAAAGCGUGGAUACCCAUCAACGAAGUUUUGAUAUUGGAAUUCAGAUUGGCUAUCAGCGACGCAAUAAGGAUGUGUUGGCUUGGGUUAAAAAACGCAGAAGAACUAUUCGUCGAGAAGAUUUGAUCAGCUUCCUGUGUGGAAAAGUUCCUCCACCACGAAACUCUAGAGCUCCCCCAAGACUGACUGUAGUGUCCCCUAACCGAGCUACUUCAACGGAAACUAGCUCAUCUGUAGAGACUGAUUUGCAACCCUUCCGGGAAGCCAUAGCUCUGCAUGGUCUUAGUGGUGCAAUGGCUAGUAUAAGCGUGCGUUCGAGUACCCCAGGCUCUCCUACACAUGUAAGCAGUGGAUCGAAUGCUAGUCGAAGGAGAAAUGGACUCCAUGAUGUCGAUUUGAACACUUUCAUAUCAGAAGAAAUGGCACUCCACUUGGACAAUGGUGGAACUAGAAAGCGUACCUCAGCCCAGUGUGGCGAUGUCAUUACAGACUCACCAACCCAUAAACGCAACAGAAUGAUCUAAACUGCAAACAUUUUCACACCCACCAUGCUGCUUGAAAGCCACUUGAUCCUCAACAUAUACUAUAAUUGCAAAGGAAACAUGAGGCCAUCUUCCCUUGUUCACUGUUUAAGACAAGUGAAUUCUAUAGUGGUUGCCAUAAAAGGAAGUUCUAGGUAUUUAUAGUAGAUGCCUCUUGUAAUUAUGGCUUUCUUAAAACUAUAAUCCUAGCAGAGGACAUCAGAUAUUGUGUAGUCGUUAGCAAGAUCAUCAUAGGCAAACAUAUAUCCGUUCCAAGGCUAAAAGUGACCUUAACUGUAUUUAUUCUCAAAGGGAAAGGAAAUAUCAGAUGUUUAUUUGGUUAUAGAAUGCUUUUUUUUUUUUUGGGUCCAUUUCCUGCUGUGUUGAGUAUUUUGCUUCAACAGUAUUGCCAGGUUCCUAAAAUUGUCUAAAAACAUGAUUUGGCUUCCAUUUUUGCAGCUGCACUGUACCAUGCACCUGGUUUCUAUAUAGUAACAGUGUGCAAUUCUAAUUAUUGGACUGUGCCCUGUUUUUAGUUUUCAAAUCAAUUUCUAAUUCUGGUGAUUGUGUGAUGUAAAGAGGUGCUAUGAUGGUCAUGCAAUUAAUACUAAAUAUUGAAUCAAUGCCCAGAGCUUUAUUGGAUUCACUUUGUGUGUGUUAGUGCUCUAAAGUAGCAGUAUUAUUAUUAAACUGUCCCCAGAGUAACCCUGUAGGCCUAAAGUACUCAGUUUUAAGACAAACACUACUUCCCAUGCGGGGUACUUUCCUUAUGGUAAAUGUAAACAUGUAGACUGCAUUCGAGGUGACCUAAAGUAGAGAGGUCAUGAACUUUGAGAAUGGGCUUCCUUUUUGGUUCAGUAUUAGUGAGAGGGAGAGGGAGAUGGAUGGUGGGGUAGGUUUUCUAGUCUAUCAUUUUACAUUUUUCAUGGAGUCCCUGCUUAGUGCAGUUUCCAUUGGAAUGGGUGGAAGAUGAUAAAGCUCUCUUUUUUAUCUACUAAUAAUGUGAUUGCAACUUAAAAUAGCAAAACCCAACUCUCCCUGUCCCUCCAAUCCCUCUCCUAAAAAGUUCAGUUUGGAAUCUCAUUCUGGAAAAGAUGGAAUCGCAUGGAGAUUCUCUAGCUGUUAGGUAGACCUAAAUAAAAAGUUCUCAAUAGAUUCCUCUUUUGAGUAAAUAUAAGACCUCUUGUAGCUACAAUGUUUUAGAGCAUGUUUCAUCUUCAUUUUUAAUAUCCUGAACUGAAUGAUAGUGUUUUUUUAGAUGAAGAACUGAUGUCAGCCUGCCAGGUACUGUAAUUUAUUCUAUCAUAUUAUUAUAUUAUAUAUCAAGUAGGACAGUGAAAAAUGUUUCCUUGCAAACUUGUAGUCCAGUAUCAGUUACUUCCUAUUUUUAUCCUUAAAAGACCAUUGCAAAUCAGUGUAAGGGUUUUUCCAGUAAUUACUCACAGCACUUUGUUAAAGUUUGCAAUUUCUUCAGCCAUUUAAUAAUAUCUUUCUGUGAAGAAACUUUGCUGAGUUAACCAUAAAUGUUCAUUCAUUGACUGGGUGGGAUGUGAAUGGAAUGUUAGAAAUGUUGUGUGAAUUGAAGUUCUGUAUUCAUUAUAGAUGUAGCCCUUAUUUAAAAAAGUGAAUUCCAUACUAAAACUAGGAAUGAAAGUGAGAGAUUUCUAAACUUUUGCGAAAGUGGGUCAUUUUUUGUUUGACUAUAAUAGCAGGAAGAAUUAUAGCAAUCUGUCAUUUUACCUGAAACAGACAAGCCUAUGUAUUAUGAAUACUUUCAAGCUUCCCUUUGGAAUAUACAAGACAUGCGUUUGGAGUUACCUUUGUUUUUCUAUCGUAAAUUUAGAUUCUGGAAUUGGGGUUUGGUGGUGCAAUGUGUUGCUCACAAGUGGCCAGAACUCCUAUUCCUAAAAGGAUUUUGAGAUGGAGGAACACAUAUUUAAUUCCCCUUUAUGCCUUGGUUCUUGCUCCUCUUUCCACGUUGGAUAACAAUUUUUUGGUUGUUUUGUUUAAGUUGGUGCUCUGAAGCUUAAUCUCAGUACCCUUUACUCUGAAUUGUCAAAUUUUGAUAAAACGUGCCAUUUUCUUUGGUAAGAGAAAGCAGGUCUUAAUGUCUGCCAGAACACAAUUUAUAUGCCUUAUUGGCUUCAUUAAACUUUUAGAAAACUUUAGCAUUUGUUACUUUUUUCCAUUGCGUUUACUUUCAAAUGCACCUAAUGAAUUUGUCACCCAGUCGCAACUUUUCCCUUCUCUGUCCCAUUGCUUUCUCCUUUCCCCGACGCACAGAAUAAACAUGAAGCUCAGCAGUAGAAGCGUAAUGAUUUCCCUCAGGAAAAACUUCUGACAGCUAGGUUUUUCAAGGGUUUCCCUGUGCUAGCUGAGAUGCAAAACAAAUCAUGGAAGAUUGCAUACCUGUGUGGUAUUUUAAAAACAAGUUGACUUUUUCAGUUUCUUGAACGGUUAAGGGUGGAUUUAAAAACUAGACAGUUUAGUUUUGGGGAACAGAAGCUCUCUUCGUCUUAAGCCAGAUUCUCUGAUUCUUUUAGACGUCAUAGCUCCUUAGUUCUGCUCCUGUCGCCCUAACUUGGCAUGGGCAAGUUGAAGUUCAUCCUUAGACUGCAGCGUUCUGAGCAUGGCUGAAGUAUUAAAAUGUUUAAUAUUUUUUAGAGCAAAAUUGUUGGAAAGCAUUUGGCUGAAUCUAAAGACCUGCAGUCAGAUUCUUCAAUGUGGUUUACCCAACUGGAGUAGUGAUAAACACCUUAAUCAUAAAAUGAAUAAAAACAAAAAAACCAUGGGGCUUGUCUGCAGUUUUGUUUUGGUCAUCACAUCUGAAUAACUUUUUGAUGCAAUCAAAUGAAGUUUAGGCUUUUAAAAAAGAAUUAGCUUUCUAAAUGUUUUUUUCUAAGGGCUACUGGAACUCAUUAAACUCGAAUAAUUGUGGCUUUGGGCCUGAAGAUUUCCAUUCAACAGUGAAAACUGGCUAACUUCCUUUAUAGUGAGAGGGAUGGCCAACAUCCAACCCAGAGGGCUAGUCAGCCUCAGAGGCCAGUGCAAGACGCCAAGAGAUGAUUUUGAAAUGGGGCCAUAAGUUUAGAAAAUUAUGAACAGAAUGAUUGAGUUUUUGGCCUGGCUACUACCUCUAGUGGUGACUACGUCAGCAGAUUAAUCUCAUUGCAUUUUACUUUAUGUAGUAUGUUGUAACCUGGUGCUUCAUUCAUUAGAUUGGUGACUGAGGUAUUUAGUCAUGGUGAGGAUGGGAAUCUUCAGAGAUACAUUCUGGAUUUGUGGAAUAAAGUGACUAGAAAGGUUCUUCCAGAGCAACCCCUUGUUUAAAGUUAUAAGUGUUUAUGGUACCUGCUACCCCUUCUGGAAAGUUGUCGGCUUUGAUGGUUUAGAUGACCUUACCCCAUAAGGCCAGCUUCUAGCCUCCCUUUGGAAUAUUUGAGGUGUGUGAUGUUUUAGUGGGGGCAGCAUUUGAGAGACGAGCAGGCCCGAGCACCCAGGCUGGCUGUCAGACCGUGUGUUGUGCUGUUGGGUUUGAUGGGAUGAGAUAUCCAGGGUUUUACUUCCUAUAAUGGGAUCUGCAGGCUCCUUGUGAAGUUCAGUUAGACAGUAGCCUGUGACGUAGCAAGUCAAGUUUUCGAUGGCCCCUCAUUUUUUUUUUAUUUAGUGCUUAAAAAAAAGAUUUAAAACAGCAAAAAUCAAGCCACACAGCAGCUUAUAGUAUAUACAGGUCUUUUAUACAUUAGAAGUAAUAUGGUGAAAUCUUUUUUUUUUUUUUUUUUUUUUGUGAUGGAGUUUCACUCUCUCACCCAGGCUGGAGUGCAGUGGCACGAUCUUGGCUCACCACAACCUCUGCCUCCUGGGUUCAAGCAAUUUUCAUGCCUCAGCCUCCCGAGUAGCUGGUAUUACAGGUGCCUGCCACCACACCUGGCUAUUUUUUGUAUUUUUGUUAGAUACGGGGUUUCAAAUAUGGUGAAAUCUUGUGACAGAAUAGUAUUCCCUUGUACAGAUAAGCCUUGAUGCAGGUUACAGAUUUUUUAUAAUUAGUAAUGCAGCAGUGGAGUGUUUUCUUUUUCUUGUUUUUUGAGAUGGAGUCUCUGUCGCUGGAGUGCGGUGGUGCGAUCCCAGCUCACCGCAAUCUCUGCCUCCCGGGUUCAAGCGAUUCUCCUGCCUAUAACUACAGGUGUGCGCCACCACGCCCAGCUAAUUUAAUUUUGAAUUUUUAGUAGAGACGGGAUUUCACCAUGUUGGCCAGGCCAGUCUUGAAUUCCUGACCUUAAGUGAUCUGCCCGCCUUGGCCUCCCCAAGUGCUGGGAUUACAGGCAUGAGACACUGCGCCUGGCCUAUGUUUUAAGUUUCUCUAUGACAAAUUUCUGUAGAUGAACUAUCUGGGUCAAAAAAAUUCAUCUAUAAAAUACUGAUGGGUCUUGCCAAAGUACCUUCUGCAAGGUACCAGUUAAUACUUCCAUCAGAAAGUAAGAGCGCCUGUUCCCUUACAUCGUAGCCAGUGUUGGGUAUUUAUACUUCCUUUGGCAGAAGUGACCUUUCAGUUUUAAUCUGUUUUUUACCUGCUCGUAUGAAGGAAGACUUUUUGCUUGAUAUCACGUGGGUUUGAAUGCUGACUCUACUACCAGGUCUGGGAACCUAGGUAAGUUUGCCUCUCUGGGCUGUUUUCUCAUCUGUGAAAUAAAUAGAAAACAUAGAAAAAUAAAUUAAAAAAUGUGAA